AUGGAGAUUCCUUCUAAAAUAAGCGGGCUUAAGAAAACAGAAGAACACAGCGGACACCAGGACUCUAAGAUAGCGUCAGUUGUACCAGUGAAGGACAAGAAACUUCUGGAGGUCAAACUGGGGGAGCUGCCAAGCUGGAUCUUGAUGGGGGACUUCAGCCCUAGUGGCAUUUUCGGAGCGUUUCAAAGAGGUUACUACUGGUACUACAAGUACAUCAAUGUGAAGAAGGGGAGCAUCUCGGGGGUUACCAUGGUGCUGGCAUGCUACGUGCUCUUCAGCUACUCCUUUUCCUACAAGCAUCUCAAGCACGAGUGGCUCCGCAAAUACCACUGA